AAGCCUCCAAGUUCCCUGAGAGCUACCGGCCAGGGGUCGGGAGGCUAUGGGAGCUCAGGGCAGGCACCUCCCAUGCUCCCGCGGGAGCCACCAGGACAUGAAGGUCAUAGGCCUCUCCUCUCCUCCUCUUCCUGUUUGACCUGAAUGCCCCCAGGCCAACUGCCUCAAGGAUUCCAUUUGAGAAGAUGCAGGCUGGGUGUGUGGGGAGCAGUAGAGGGGCUGGUGUGUGCACAUAUGUGCACAGCUCAGGACAGAGGCUCCCUGGACUUGGGGCGGGGGCACUAGGGCCCCAACUCUAACCCUCGUUCUGCCCUGUUGACCUCUGCUCUCUGGACCAAAAAUGGAGGACUCAGUCUAGACUAGUUCUUAGGGUCUAGGAGCCACCUUAAGUUAUGUUUAUAUGCAAAGGCCAUUUUUCUGAGAGGCCAUAGCUUUCAUCAGUGUGCCAAAAAGCGUGAGAUCCUCUGCUCUAAAAGCCUCUGCCCCAGCGCUGCCUAGUUUCAGAGCCCCCGAUGGCCUCACAUGGGGUUUUAGAGCAGGCAGAGAAGCUGCAAUGGGGCCACCAGCCAGUCCUCAGAGUCCUGGGUUAAGGCCUCCUCUCCAGGAGGCCCUGUGUAAAGGUUUUCUCUGUUGCCUGGAGGCAGGAGUGAACUGGUAGGCAGGAAACCCUGAGGGUACCUAGGAGGCCCCUAGCCUGUGGGUUGGGGAGGGAAGACAGGACCCCUGGGGCCACUGAAAUGGUGGAGCUCUCAGAGACCUGAGUUCUGGUCCCUUCUGCCACUUUUUGGGCAGAUCCCGUCUUCCCACAGGCCCUGUGUCUUGCUCAGUCCACGUGACUCUGCUUUCUCAUCCUAGGCCUCAGGUGGGUGGCAGGCCCUUUCCUGCUUGCCCUCUGCCCUCCCUCUCUCUGGCCCUGCCCAGUCUCUGCCAAUCUGUGUACCUCCCAGGAGCCGGGACACUCCCUGAGUCCUCUGGGAGCCCUUAAGCCACACUGAGAACACAGACCCUGGGAGAAGCAGCCAGCAGUGAGGAAUCCUGGAACCCCUUCCCAGGGAGAGCCUUCCCAUGACCCCCAUGAAGAGAUCAGUGCAAACACAGGUGUCAGAGCCCUUCAUGGAGUCCUGGGGUGAGGAGUCCCUGCCGGAGCUACCCGCAGAGCAGUCCCUGACGGAGUACUCUGACCUCGAGGAGGCUCCCUCGGCGCACACUCUCUAUGUGGGCCAUCUGAACCCCCAGUUCUCAGUGCCGGUGCUUGCCUGCCUGCUGCGAGACACCCUGGAGCGGCUGGAGAUGCCGGUGGCGCGGGAGCACAUUGAAGUGGUGAGGCGGCCGCGGAAGGCCUAUGCACUGGUGCAGGUGACUGUCCACAGGGACACCCUGGCCUCCCUCCCCUGGCGCCUGCAGACGGCCCUGGAGGAGCACCUAAUCCUCAAGGAGCUGGCAGCCCGUGGGAAGGACCUGCUAUUGAGUGAGGCCCAAGGGCCCUUCAGCCACAGAGAGGAGAAGGAGGAGGAGGAGGAGGACAGUGGCCUGAGCCCUGGCCCCAGUCCAGGCUCUGGUGUCCCGCUGCCCACCUGGCCUACACACACGCUGCCUGAUAGGCCCCAGGCCCAGCAGCUGCAGAGCUGCCAGGGCCGGCCCAGCGGCGUGUGCUCCGACAGUGCCAUUGUGCACCAGCAGAUCGUGGGCAAGGACCAGCUCUUCCAGGGUGCCUUCCUGGGCAGCGAGACCCGCAAUAUGGAGUUCAAGCGGGGUAGCGGCGAGUACCUCAGCCUGGCCUUCAAGCACCACGUGCGGCGCUACGUGUGCGCCUUCCUCAACAGCGAGGGCGGCAGCCUGCUCGUGGGAGUAGAGGACAGCGGCCUGGUGCAGGGCAUCCGCUGCAGCCACCGUGACGAGGACCGCGCACGCCUGCUGGUGGACUCCAUCCUGCAGGGCUUCAAGCCUCAGAUCUUUCCCGAUGCCUACACUCUCACCUUCAUCCCUGUGAUCAGUACCUCGGAGACCAGCGUCCCCCUCAAGGUGAUCCGCCUGACCGUGCACACCCCCAAGGCCCAGAGCCAGCCGCAACUCUACCAGACAGACCAGGGGGAGGUGUUUCUGCGGCGCGACGGGAGCAUCCAGGGCCCGCUGUCUGCCAGCGCCAUCCAGGAGUGGUGCAGGCAGAGGUGGCUGGUGGAGCUGGGCAAGCUGGAAGAGAAGAUGAAGGCGCUGAUGAUGGAGAAGGAGCAGCUCCAGCAGCAGCUGCAGCAGCACGGGCCUGUGUCCUGCACCUGCUGUGUCCUGUGAGGGCCCUGGGGAGCAGGCAGGACGGCACGGCACUCUCCACCUGAGACCCAGGGAUUUCCUGUUUGAGUGUAAGGCCAACCAGUAAAGCCCAUGCGGGCUGCUGAGAGGCGGACAGGGACUCCUUCAACAUGGCACAUGAGCAGGCACCCAUGUGGCUUCAACCCUGACAGACCCAUCUGUGUAGCCAAGAAACUGCUCUCAGCCCUGUCCCCAAAUGACCUUACUUUCAGAAAGAAUGUGUAAAACCCUGCCCAGAGCUCCCCUAGGGCUAAGCUAUAAGGGAUUGUCCUUCUCCCUAAAAUGCUCAUUUGGCCCAGGCUGAGGUCUGUGACUCCAGUUGGCUACACAGUGCCAGAAAGGAAUCUGUCAUCUCAGGAAAGCCCCUCAAAGAUGGCGAGGCAUAUUUGAUGACUGUGGUUACAGGGCAAGAGGCCACCCUGCAGCCCCCACCCCUGACUUGCUGGAACUUGUGACUGUCAAAGCUCCAUUAAUAAAUUACAUGCACCUGG